AGACAAAAGGCGGCGGCGGGAGCGGGCGGGAGGCGGAGCGGCGCCGCGAGGGCCUCAAGGUGACACCCGCCCCCGGCCCCGGCCCCCCCCGGCCCGGCCCCCCAGCCUGCCUCCCACCCUCAGCCCCCAGCCCCUUACUCCCGGUGCCCUUUCCGGGCCCCCUCCCCCGGCGGGGGGUGGGGAGCAGCGAGGGCCCCGCCCCCUCCCGUCCUCUCCCCAGGGCCCGCGCAGGAUGCCCCCGGCCCCUGGCAGCCCCCCGGGAGGUCCUGAGCUCGACGCGCCCCCUCUACGCCAUGUCCCCCCCUGGCUCGGCCGCGGGAGAGAGCGCCGCCGGCGGCGGCGGCGGCGGUGGCGGCCCCGGGGUCUCGGAGGAGCUCACGGCGGCGGCGGCAGCGGCGGCGGCGGACGAGGGCCCCGCCCGAGAGGAGCAGCGUCCCAUCCAGCCCUCUUUCACCAAGUCCCUCUGCCGUGAGUCCCACUGGAAGUGCCUCCUGCUCUCGCUGCUCAUGUACGGCUGCCUGGGGGCAGUGGCCUGGUGCCACGUCACCACAGUGACGCGCCUCACCUUCAGCAGCGCCUACCAGGGCAACAGCCUCAUGUACCAUGACAGCCCCUGCUCCAACGGCUAUGUCUACAUCCCCCUGGCCUUCCUGCUCAUGUUGUACGCCGUCUACCUGGUGGAGUGUUGGCACUGCCAAGCCCGCCAUGAGCUGCAGCACCGUGUUGAUGUGAGCAGUGUGCGGGAACGUGUGGGCCGCAUGCAGCAAGCCACGCCCUGCAUCUGGUGGAAGGCCAUCAGCUACCACUAUGUCCGCCGCACCCGCCAGGUCACCAGAUACCGCAAUGGAGACGCCUAUACCACCACCCAGGUCUACCACGAACGCGUCAACACGCACGUGGCGGAGGCUGAGUUCGACUACGCGCGCUGCGGCGUUCGCGACGUGUCCAAGACGCUGGUGGGGCUGGAGGGCGCGCCGGCCACGCGGCUGCGCUUCACCAAGUGCUUCAGUUUCGCCAGCGUGGAGGCCGAGAACGCGUACCUGUGCCAGCGCGCGCGCUUCUUCGCAGAGAACGAGGGCCUAGACGACUACAUGGAGGCACGCGAGGGCAUGCACCUCAAGAACGUGGACUUCCGUGAGUUCAUGGUGGCCUUCCCGGACCCGGCCCGGCCGCCCUGGUACGCCUGCUCGUCGGCCUUCUGGGCCGCGGCGCUGCUCACGCUGUCGUGGCCGCUGCGAGUGCUGGCCGAGUACCGCACGGCCUACGCGCACUACCACGUGGAGAAGCUAUUUGGCCUGGAGGGCCCGGGCUCGGCCAGCAGCGCAGGCGGUGGCCUCAGCCCCAGCGAUGAGCUGCUGCCCCCGCUCACCCACCGCCUGCCGCGGGUCAACACAGUAGACAGCACGGAGCUCGAGUGGCACAUCCGCUCCAACCAGCAGCUGGUGCCCAGCUACUCUGAGGCGGUGCUCAUGGACCUGGCGGGGCUCGGGACGCGCUGCGGCGGGGCAGGCGGCGGCUACGCGCCCUCGUGCCGCUACGGUGGGGUAGGCGGCCCGGGCGCGGCGGGCGUGGCUCCCUACCGGCGCAGCUGCGAGCACUGCCAGCGCGCCGUCAGCAGCUCGUCUAUCUUCUCGCGCAGCGCCCUAAGCAUCUGCGCCAGCCCGCGGGCCGGCCCGGGGCCCGGUGGGGGCGCGGGCUGCGGGGGCAGCCGCUUCUCGCUGGGCCGUCUCUACGGCUCCCGGCGCAGCUGCCUGUGGCGCAGCCGCAGCGGGAGCGUCAACGAGGCCAGCUGCCCCACGGAGCAGACGCGGCUGUCCAGCCAGGCCAGCAUGGGGGACGACGAGGACGACGACGAGGAGGAGGCCGGGCCGCCGCCGCCCUACCACGACGCCCUCUACUUUCCGGUCCUCAUCGUCCACCGGCAGGAGGGGUGUCUGGGCCACAGCCACCGGCCGCUGCACCGCCACGGCUCCUGCGUAGAGACCUCACUGUGACCUCCGGCCCCGGAGUGGCCCGCGCCGUCCUCCCGCCUGCCCCUCGCCGGACUGUGCUCCCUCUGCGACGCAGGGCGAGUCACCACGGUGACUGAGGCCGCGCGGGGGGCAGGGAAAGGGAGGUGAGGGCCGCAAGACAGGCCCGGAUGGGGCCGAGACCCCCGCUGUCCCUGUACAUAAAGAGACCGAUGGGUGGGAGGGGGUCGGCUGCUCCCCGAGAUCCCCCUGGCAGAGUCAUUCUUCCAGCCCCAACCCUGAGUUCCUAAAGGGACACCUCCCUCCUGUCCAGCCCUUCAACAGAUCUUCUGUUAGAUGACAACCGUGCCGUGGGCCCCGCGUUGGGCCUUGUCUGAAGGGAGAGGCCCUGGCAUGCGGAUGGGAGAUUUAGAGGCUGUGGAGAAGGGAACUUGGGGCUUUCCUUCCUUCGUGGCCUCACUCCCCUGGGGCCUCUCUCUAUGGAGGGGGCAAUGGUUUGGUGACCAGCAGGCUGGAUUCCAACUAGCUAAUGCAUUCAGCAGGUCUGAGGCUGGGGCCAGGUGUCAGCCCUAGGCCUCCAUCCAACACCGUGGAAAUGUUGCUGCCCUCUUCUUGGCGCUGACCCCAAGAUUGGGGUUUCCUUUCUGCCGCUCCCUCCACUGUUGUUUAUCUAACUGGGCCCCCACUCCAGGUCCAGAGGGACUGUGCUCACUGCACAGACAUCACUCACCUUCCGCUCCCCAGUCCUGCAGAGCUGUUGCCAGGGUGCAGUGGGGAGGGGAGUGAAAUGUGGAGGACUGUGUACCUCAGUCCUCUCUCUAAACUCCUCAGCCUCCCAACAGGGGCCUCCUCACCUGGGUUCUGAGUGUAUACCCCUUUUAGAGAGUGAGAUGCCACCCGGGCAGCACUCGUUAAAGCUGGCCAGCACGAGUGACUAAGGGGAGAGAGCAUGACAUAGACCUGGGUGGCAACGGGGACCUCUGGAAGCAGGUGGGAGUAAGAGAGGAGAGGGCAGUGGAGGGUAGAGGAAAAGGACCUCCAGAGGUGGGGUGUCUGUGGGGGCGGCCUUUGCCUCCCUAAACCUGUGCGGAGGAGUGGAGUGUGCUUGUCGCUCAAACACAUCUCUGGGGGACUGAGGACGUUGUCACAAGCCCCAACUGGAGAAAUAAUUCCAAUGGCAGGGUCAGAGGCAAGCAUUCUCUAAAUCUUGCCCAACCCUUCCAUCCUUCCCUAUCCUAUGAGCUGAAGCCCUGCUGUGUGUCGCAGGGUCUUCAAAGGGGCAUCCUGCCACCACCCCAGGGCGCUGGCCCCACGUCCUGUUCCCCUAAAGCUCUGACACCGCCUUCUCUCCGUGUGCUCCCCCCACCACCUCCACCCUGAUGUGCUUCAGUGUGCAUGUCUGUGAACAGCCCUCCUGCCCUGCCAACUCCCCUGGCUAAAGUCUCCCCAGCAGAUUUAGCACCCAGGGAUUGAGCUCACAUUUCAGGCUAGAGAGGAUAACCCUUGGGCCACCCACAUCUCUCACCCCUGAUGCUUCUUACUUCGCCUGAGCCAUCAGAACUCCUCCUUACCCUCCUUCAGCCCCUCUCAUCUUCCUUCAGCCCAGCCAGGCCUGCACCACCAACUGUGUGGCCUCCACCUAUGCAACAUCGCCUCUGGCUCCCCUUCCCUUCUUCCUAGCGGGGAGUGCGAGGGGCCCAAAUUGUGGGGAUACCAUGGCCCAUGGCUUCUAAAGGGUUUAGCUUUACUUUCAGGUAGAGAUGGCUGAGUGAGGAGGGAGAAGAGGCUAGAGAGAGGGAGGCUUGGGCAGGGGAAACAGCUGCCCACCAGGUUUUCCUGGACAGCAGUGCCCACCUGCCUACUAGCACUGAACCUGCCUGGACCCUGAGUCUGUGCUCCUUGGGGGCCUGGCGUUUGGAGCACCCUUCUUUCCUCUGAAUGGACAUCUGUGAGGUACAGGUGGUGAGCUGCAGCCUCAGGCUCCAUUUCUUAGCCAGCUGGCACCUGGAUGUCAUGCUUUGUGUGGGGACAGCCUGGCCACCUCAGGGCUCCAAGGAAGGAGGAACGUGGCUCCUCCUCCCUCAGGCCUGUUCCUGAGACAGAGCCUGGUCUCACAAGAGGGGAAGGGGGACCUCUAUUAUUAUUUUUGCCUGUAUUGACCAUUUCUGCCUAGGUCGUCUCAGACAGCCUCAUCUCCCACACAUGCACAGACUUAGAGAGAAACCAAUUCUUUGGUCUAUUUUCUUGGUAGCUUUACUGAUUGCCAGGGAAAAUGAAAACCAGAAAAUUAAUUAAUCUCUAAAAUUAAACUUUACACUGAAUGUUCUUGUUUCUCUAAUUAGAACUUCUGCUAGCAGCUGUGGCUAUACACACACACACACACACACACACCCUCACACCUACACGUUUGCACUCCGGAACUGUCAGAGGGUGUCAGGCACAGACAGACUCUAGGUUGCCUAGACAGGCACACACAUGCAGUCACUCCCAAGCCCCCUUUGGUGCUCUGCUCAGCGCCUGCUUAGCGGAAGGAGUCCCUGGAGAGCAGGCACUCCUGGACUGGGGUUGUAGCCCAUGACCUGCCCUUUGGGGACACAGUUCUGGAGGCUCUGGGCCAAUGAAUCAGCCCAAGGAGGAUGGGCAAUGGCGCUCAGCCUGAAUCAGUCAGCUAGGUCUCUUGUGGCCCUGGGGGCUGAUGUGAUUCCUGUAGGUGUGGCCCCAGGGUGGACAGCUACAGAGUGAUGGGGGACUCAUGUAGGGCACCUGGAAGGCUCCAUGUGUCCUGGGGACAAGGGCUUGUGGGGUGGGCUGGGCCUGGCUGGGGAGAAGACAGGUCUCUGUCAAUUGGGUGCAUCACACUGUGGCCUUUUUGUCGUGGAUUUAAGCGCAAAGAUUGUACAAAUCAAACUGGUGGAUAAUAAAGUCGUGGAUGACUCACUGA